AUCUCUUGAGACUUCACUUCAGCUUCACUGACUUCUGGAUUCUCCUCUUGAGUAAAAGGACUCAGCCAACUAUGAAGUUUUUUGUUUUUGCUUUAAUCUUGGCUCUCAUGCUUUCCAUGACUGGAGCUGAUUCACAUGCAAAGAGACAUCAUGGGUAUAAAAGAAAAUUCCAUGAAAAGCAUCAUUCACAUCGAGGCUAUAGAUCAAAUUAUCUGUAUGACAAUUGAUAUCUUCAGUAAUCACGGGGCAUGAUUAUGGAGGUUUGACUGGCAAAUUCGCUUUGGACUCGUGUAUUCUCAUUUGUCAUACCGCAUCACACUACCACUGCUUUUUGAAGAAUUAUCAUAAGGCAAUGCAGAAUAAAAGAAAUACCAUGAUUUAGUGAAUUCUGUGUUUCAGGAUACUUCCCUUCCUAAUUAUCAUUUGAUUAGAUACUUGCAAUUUAAAUGUUAAGCUGUUUUCACUGCUGUUUCUGAGUAAUAGAAAUUCAUUCCUCUCCAAAAGCAAUAAAAUUCAAGCACAUUAUUAUGUG